AGACCCAGCGGCGAGCGCAGCGGGGGCGGCGGGCCGGGGACCGGGCAGCACCGGGCGCGCGGAGCGGGCGCGCCGCCAACGCGGUCACGUGCGCGGCCCCUCCUCUCGCGCCGGCCUCCCCCGCGCCGCGCUCUCCAUUCAUAAAUUCUCCGCCUGCUCCGCGGCCACCGGGCGCCGGAGCCAGCCGCGAGCGCCACGCAGCCGCCCGCCGCCAGCCCGCCGCCCAUGGGCCGCUCGUCCCGGCGCUGAGGGCCCUCCUCCCCAGUUCAGAAUGCAGCCCACAGCCACCAUGGCCACAGCCGCCACCACCACCACCACCACCACUGCCACAGUAGCCCUGACGACGUCGUGGGACAAUGCCACUGGACGCCCCACGGCAGAGCCAGACCCCAUCCUGGACAACUACGUGCUGCUGGUGGUGGUGAUGUCGCUGUUCGUGGGGGGCACGCUGGUGGUGUUGUCUGGCGUCCUGCUCCUCUGCAAGCGCUGCUGGGACGUCCACCAGCGCCUCAACAGGGCCAUGGAGGAAGCGGAGAAGACCACCACCACCUACCUGGACAACGGCACCCACCCAGCCCAAGACCCCGACUUCCGGGGAGAGGACCCCGAGUGCCAGGAUGCGGAGACCGAACGCUUCCUGUCCACCAGCUCCACGGGCCGCCGGGUCUCCUUCAAUGAGGCGGCGCUGUUUGAGCAGAGCCGCAAGACGCAGGACAAGGGUCGCCGGUACACACUGACGGAGGGGGACUUCCACCACCUGAAGAAUGCCCGGCUCACGCACCUGCACCUGCCGCCCCUCAAGAUUGUCACCAUCCACGAGUGUGACUCAGGCGAGGCCAGCUCAGCCACCACGCCCCACCCGGCCACCUCUCCCAAGGCCACUCUGGCCAUCUUCCAGCCCCCGGGGAAGGCCCUCACCGGCCGCUCUGUGGGCCCCAGCUCCGCCCUGCCAGGUGACCCCUACAACUCAGCCGCGGGCGCCACUGACUUCGCAGAGAUCAGCCCCUCGGCAUCUAGCGACUCUGGGGAAGGCACCUCGUUGGAUGCCGGUACCAGGAGCACCAAGGCUGGAGGGCCCGGGGCUGCAGCAGGGCCUGGGGAGGCGGGCCCGGGAUCCGGGGCAGGUACCGUUCUGCAGUUCCUCACCCGCCUGCGCCGCCAUGCCAGCCUGGAUGGGGCCAGCCCCUAUUUCAAGGUCAAGAAGUGGAAGCUGGAGCCCAGCCAGCGGGCAGCCAGUCUGGACACGAGAGGUUCCCCCAAGCGGCACCACUUCCAGCGGCAGCGGGCAGCCAGUGAGAGCACGGAGCAGGAGGAGGGGGAUGCCCCCCAGGAGGACUUCAUCCAGUACAUUGCCCGGGCGGGCGACGCCGUGGCCUUCCCGCACCCCCGCCCCUUUCUGGCCAGCCCGCCCCCUGCUCUCGGCAGGUAUUUUUCAGUAGAUGGAGGUGCUAGGGGUGGACCUGUGGGCCCUUGCCCCCCUUCGCCCCCCCCUAGGCGGCCCAGGGAGCGCUCUCCAGGCCCCGUGGACACGCGCUCGCCUGCCUCCAGCGGCAAGGCCCCUCCCAGAGGCGGACUCACUGGGGCCACCUCUCCAGCAUGGACCAGAGGAGGGAAGCAGGGAGAGACUGGGUAAGGGUAGGGCGGUGGGUGGGGAGGAGGGGCCCCCCGAGGAUGGCGCUGGUACUGCUGCUUGCUGGUGGAGUCCGAGGCCUGAAGGGUUCUGCUGUGGUCCCAGGCCCUCUCCCACCCCCGCCCCGCCCAUGCUCCCAAGGCUGGGCAGACUCCUCUCAGAAGCUGCUGUGACCACUCCGGCCAGCAGCACCCCUCCCCCAACCCAAGGGCAACUUCCCUGAAGCCCAGGGCCCACGUCGGUGGGAUGGGAAUGGGGCGUGGGGCUGGGGCAGAGCAGGGUUCCUGGGGCAGCCCUGGUAUGGCGGGUGACCCUCACGUCUGUGCACUGUCCUCCUGCUGGUUAUCCAGCAUGGGUGGGCAGAGAGCCCUAGCCUGGAGCAGGGGCUGAGCUGGACUCAACCGCGUCCAGUCCAUCCCCUGCGGCUCCCACGUCCACUGGGAGGCUGGGAAAACGUGACUCCCGGAGAGAAGCAUGUUGACUUUUCCUGGGGGCUUCCAAGGGAGGGGGCCCCGCCGUCUGCAGUCCAGCAUGGAGGCACCCUGCUUAAUAAGCAGGCGCCACAGCUCAGGGUCAAUGCAAGACGCAUCCCCUGCAAAACACACUGGCUCAUUUUAAAGCUCUCACCUUCCAAGGCCCGCCCGAGUCCCAAGUCCCACCCGCGUCCACCCUCCCUGAUCCAGAGGCGGGAUGGCCGGCCGGGUAGGGGGCGCGGGGCUCGGCGGGGCUCUGACGGCGCGGCCUGGCUUGCAGGCUAGAGGCGGCCGAGGCAGCGGGAGGAGCGAGCCCCGAUUCCCCCCCGGAGCGCGGCGCGGGCAGCGCGGGGCCUGAGCAGCAGCAGCCGCCACUGGAGCCGGACGCCGAGCGGGACGCGGGCCCCGAGCAGGCCCAGACCAGCUACCGCGACCUGUGGAGCCUGCGCGCCUCGCUUGAGCUGCAUGCGGCCGCCUCGGACCACAGCAGCAGCGGCAACGACCGCGACUCGGUGCGCAGCGGCGACAGCUCGGGCUCAGGCUCCGGGGGCGCGGCGCCCGCCUUCCCGCCGCCCUCCCCGCCCGCGCCGCGGCCCAAGGACGGCGAGGCGCGCCGGCUGCUGCAGAUGGACAGUGGCUACGCCAGCAUCGAGGGCCGCGGCGCAGGCGACGACACCGAGCCACCUGCCGCGCCCGCCCGGCCCCGCAGCCCGCGCGCCUGGCCCCGCCGCCCGCGCCGCGACUACAGCAUCGACGAGAAGACGGACGCGCUGUUCCACGAGUUCCUGCGCCACGACCCGCACUUCGACGACACGCCGGCUGCCGCGCGACACCGCGCCCGCGCGCACCCGCACGCCCGCAAACAGUGGCAGCGUGGCCGGCAGCACAGCGACCCCGGCGCCCGCGCGGCCCCGGCCCUGGCCGGAACCCCGGCACCGCCUGCCGGCGCGGCCCGACCCGCGCGUGCGCCCUUGCGGCGCGGCGACAGCGUGGACGGCCCGCCCGACGGUCGCACCCUGGGCGGCGCCGGCGACGACCCCGCCAUCCCCGUCAUCGAGGAGGAGCCGGGCGGCGGGGGGUGCCCCGGCUCGGGCCUGUGCGUCCUACCAUCCGGGUCGGUGCUGGACAAGCUGGCGGCUGGCCUCGACGAGAGACUCUUUCCGCCGCGCCUCGCCGAGCCCGUCGUGGCGACUCCCGCGUUGGUCGCCGCCGCCCCCACGUCCCCCGACCACAGCCCGGCCUAAGUCCCGCGUCCUGGGCCCAUCUCUCUGGCAGCUUCUCCGGCGCCGCACGGGGCCUCGGCGGCGGGAGAGACGUGGGGGCGCGACGCCCCGACGCGAAUGCGCGGGGACCGCGGGCCCUUCGCGCACGCGCCGGGCGACGGAGGCGCGCUCGCCGCUUCAGGGCGCAGGCGCAGAGCCCCGGCCGCCCUCGCGCCGCCGAAGUGUGCACUGCUCUUUCCGGUGCUUGCCGGGUGCUGGGCGUCGUGAGGCGCGGGCCGCGGAGACCCCGGCUGGGCGGGAAGGAAGGGGCGUGAACGGCUCUCAGCUUCGGGCUCCUGAGGACAACGAUCACUCGCCCUCAGUCCCGGACGGGGCGGCCGCUUAGUCGCAGGGCCCGCCACCCGAGGGUCGCGCAGCCCACUGGGCCCGAUGGAGCCGCCGCGUGCCGGGCGCGUGCGCGAGCUCGCCCGGGCGGGGGCCGCGGGGCGCUAACGGUCGCAGACGAGUUCGCCGCCCUGGGCCGGGAGGCGGCUCAACACCGUGACUGCCGACCUCCGAGACCGUUUACCUCACUGCGGCGUGUGCUGGCGGCAGCCCGCGCCGCCUCCGAGCAAUAACCGCGCCGCCACCGCUGCUGCCGCCGGCCCUGAGGGAGCCGGCCCCGGCCCUCCCGCGCCCCGAGUCCCCACUGCCCUCCGCAUGUCAACGGCGCCCGCCCCGCUGCCGCCCCAUCCACGUUGAGACGCGAACAAAACCCAGACGGCCAGGUCCAAGCUUCCCAAGCUUUAUUUAUUGCCAAAUUUGGGCGGCCUCGCCCGCACGGCACCCUCCGAGUCCCCGCCGCGUCUGCACCAUCCCGCGAUGGCGUUUCUCGUGUUUUUCUUUUCUGGAUGAUAUAAAUAUUGACCGCACA